CUGUCGCUGUGGAAACCGCUAGGCCAGCGCUCGCCGGGACCUGGAAUCCCUGUACGCCGAGGUGGGAGCCGGUGGACCGGUCCCCCAGCCGGCCCCCACCUCCGCUUCCCGGUGUUUGAGGGUUCGGGCCUCCCGCCGGGGAGUUCACCCCUCGGGCUCGUCAGUAGGGCUGUGGCUGUCGCCUCUUCCUGCAGCGCCAGGCUCCGCCCGGUCUCACAGUCGGCUUAGGGGCUUUGCGUGCACUGCGGUUGGGUGGAAAAACCCACUCCUGGUUGUUUAGACGUUGGCCUGCAGACGAUGUCAUUUCUGUAUUCCUCUAAGGCAGGAAGUCAUUAUGCAACUUACACAUAUUCAUCAGAUUUCCUCUGACUUACCCGGACAUGUACAUGGGAAUGAUGUGCACUGCCAAGAAAUGUGGGAUUAGGUUUCAGCCUCCAGCUAUUAUCUUAAUCUAUGAGAGUGAAAUCAAGGGGAAAAUUCGCCAGCGCAUUAUGCCAGUUCGAAACUUUUCAAAGUUUUCAGAUUGCACCAGAGCUGCUGAACAAUUAAAGAAUAAUCCGCGACACAAGAGUUACCUAGAACAAGUAUCCCUGAGGCAGCUAGAGAAGCUAUUCAGUUUUUUACGAGGUUACUUGUCGGGGCAGAGUCUGGCAGAAACAAUGGAACAAAUUCAACGGGAAACAACCAUUGAUCCUGAGGAAGACCUGAACAAACUAGAUGACAAGGAGCUUGCCAAAAGAAAGAGCAUCAUGGAUGAACUUUUUGAGAAAAAUCAGAAGAAGAAGGAUGAUCCAAAUUUUGUUUAUGACAUUGAGGUUGAAUUUCCACAGGACGAUCAACUGCAGUCCUGUGGCUGGGACACAGAGUCAGCUGAUGAGUUCUGAUACCAAACACUCAAAACAUGCAUUGGGCUAGCAGAAUAUCCAUGUUUAUUACCAGACUGGUUCUGGAAGAAGCUGUAAAGAAUACUAAAUAUGUUGGGUUAUAGGGGAUUGACCAUGUUACUUUUCAAAACCAGGACAUUUAAAGCAUCUACUAUGUAGGUGCAUGAGGAGUAUGGGAAAAACAGAAUAAAGGAAUCUGCCUUUAAGGAGCUUACAAUCAUGCCGGGUGCGGUGGCUCACGCCUGUAAUCCCAGCACUUUGGGAGGCUGAGGCGGGUGGAUCACCUAAGGUCAGGAGUUCGAGACCAGCCUAGCCAACAUGGUGAAACCUCGCCUCUACUAAAAAUACAAAAAUUAGCCAGGCGUGGUGGCGGGUGCCUGUAAUCCCGGCUACUCAGGAGGCUGAGGCAGGAGAUUCGCUUGAACCUGGGAGGCUGAGGUUGCAGUGAGCCGAGAUCGCGCCAUUGUACUCCAGCCUGGGCGAUGAGCAAAACUCCAUCUCAAAAAAAAAAAAAAAAAAAAGCUUACAAUCUGACUGGAAGAUGUCAAAACCUGUGAAAAGCUAAUUAGCAGUAUUAAGCAACACAAACAUUAGUGCCAAAUGCAUGAUAAAGGCUAAAGAAGGCCAGAGCAUAUAUUACUGUAGAGUAGAAUAGUAAGGGAAGACUUUGUCCUUUAGUAAAGAGAUAGGAGGUGGCCUGGCCCUUGAAAUAGUAGUGUUUAGGUAGAUGCUUGUGUAGGAUUCCUGAUAAGAGCAACUGAAAAGAAGGAGAGGGGAAGUAGUAAAGGGACAAGAAACAAUUUUUUUUUUGAGGAACCAUAAGCAAAUUAUAGUUUGACAAGACAAGAUUGGGGGACAUAUAUGGUUACCAGGGAAUUACCUCUUAUGUGUUAUAUCUUUAUAUUAUUUAUCUCUGGAAAAGAGUACCCUGCAAAAUUCCCUACAGCUGCAAGCAGAUGUCACUUGAUGGACAGAGGGGGAAUUCUGCCCCUCCGGUAUCGGGAAAUACAUACUAAAGACAUUGCGAAACGCUGAACCUCUUCCCAUAAAUAAAAGGUUUGUUUGUAAAAUGGGAAAUCCACCCAUAAUAAAUGAACAAUAGGCACUGCCAGUUUAGGCCUGUUCAUGAAUGGAUCUGCAAGACAGCAUCUUCGUUUAACAACAUUAUCUGUGAUUUGAUACAUUUAUCCUUAUUACAAUAUUGUUUAGUUGGUAGAAAUUCUAUGUUUUCUACAAGGAAAUUGAUGUUUAUUAAAUAAAACUGAAAAUAAUUA